AUCAUACACGUCUAAGGGCAGAGUGAACUUCCAUCCUGAAGGCUCCGCGCUUAGUUUUCGCAGAUUAAUAGCUCACCAAGAAUUUAUCAUCUUUUCUUUCCACUAACUCGAAACCAAUCUAAAUUCUUUCCAAACAUCUUCUCAACGUAGUCUCCUUUGAUGAAAUUUACUGUUUCGGAUUCUAGACUUGGCUCUUACCAACUUAACUUUCGGUUAAUAGCUUAAUACCUCUGAUUCAGGUUUUUGCAUUUGUCAACUACCAUUGAAUGAUAAUUUCAAUGAGUUCGUUCUUAUGAGGAUCAAAUGAAAUAACAUCUGUGAAAACCUCUUACAAAGUUUAAGCAAAUAGUGCUAAGCAAUCACCAAGCGUUAACUACUAAUUUUCAGUGUUAGGCAUUAGAACUGUCAUGGCGCCUUCAAGAAGAGGUAGGAGGCCCUCUCUGCGUCCAGCAGAACCAUCUGGGGCACCUGGACCGGGCGGUGGGGUGGACAGAGAGACGAGCCCCAGCUGGGACCGAAAACAUCGACCCCUCCGAGAGGUCUCGGCCGGACCGGCGCAAGGGGAGGAGAGCGGGUGGAAGCCCACCCCAGCGAACGCCCGAGGGCCGGGCCCCGCCCACCCAGAACGUCACCCAAUGGAAACCUGCCGGCGGUGCGGCACCGCCCAUCGUUGGUCCGGGCGCCGCGAGGGCGGGGCCCGCAGUUCGGUUGCGCUGCGGAGCGCAGCUGUGAGGGAGUCGCUGUGAUCCGGGGCCCCGGAACCCGAGCUGGAGCUGAAGCGCAGGCUGCGGGGCGCGGAGUCGGGAGUGCAGGCCUGAGUGUUCCUUCCAGCAUGUCGGAGGGGGAGUCCCAGACAGUACUUAGCAGUGGCUCAGACCCAAAGGUAGAAUCCUCAUCUUCAGCUCCUGGCCUGACAUCAGUGUCACCUCCUGUGACCUCCACAACCUCAGCUGCUUCCCCAGAGGAAGAAGAAGAAAGUGAAGAUGAGUCUGAGAUUUUGGAAGAGUCGCCCUGUGGGCGCUGGCAGAAGAGGCGAGAAGAGGUGAAUCAACGGAAUGUACCAGGUAUUGACAGUGCAUACCUGGCCAUGGAUACAGAGGAAGGUGUAGAGGUUGUGUGGAAUGAGGUACAGUUCUCUGAACGCAAGAACUACAAGCUGCAGGAGGAAAAGGUUCGUGCUGUGUUUGAUAAUCUGAUUCAAUUGGAGCAUCUUAACAUUGUUAAGUUUCACAAAUAUUGGGCUGACAUUAAAGAGAACAAGGCCAGGGUCAUUUUUAUCACAGAAUACAUGUCAUCUGGGAGUCUGAAGCAAUUUCUGAAGAAGACCAAAAAGAACCACAAGACGAUGAAUGAAAAGGCAUGGAAGCGUUGGUGCACACAAAUCCUCUCUGCCCUAAGCUACCUGCACUCCUGUGACCCCCCCAUCAUCCAUGGGAACCUGACCUGUGACACCAUCUUCAUCCAGCACAACGGACUCAUCAAGAUUGGCUCUGUGGCUCCUGACACUAUCAACAAUCAUGUGAAGACUUGUCGAGAAGAGCAGAAGAAUCUACACUUCUUUGCACCAGAGUAUGGAGAAGUCACUAAUGUGACAACAGCAGUGGACAUCUACUCCUUUGGCAUGUGUGCACUGGAGAUGGCAGUGCUGGAGAUUCAGGGCAAUGGAGAGUCCUCAUAUGUGCCACAGGAAGCCAUCAGCAGUGCCAUCCAGCUUCUAGAAGACCCAUUACAGAGGGAGUUCAUUCAAAAGUGCCUGCAGUCUGAGCCUGCUCGCAGACCAACAGCCAGAGAACUUCUGUUCCACCCAGCAUUGUUUGAAGUGCCCUCGCUCAAACUCCUUGCGGCCCACUGCAUUGUGGGACACCAACACAUGAUCCCAGAGAACGCUCUAGAGGAGAUCACCAAAAACAUGGAUACUAGUGCCGUACUGGCUGAAAUCCCUGCAGGACCAGGAAGAGAACCAGUUCAGACUUUGUACUCUCAGUCACCAGCUCUGGAAUUAGAUAAAUUCCUUGAAGAUGUCAGGAAUGGGAUCUAUCCUCUGACAGCCUUUGGGCUGCCUCGGCCCCAGCAGCCACAGCAGGAGGAGGUGACAUCACCUGUCGUGCCCCCCUCUGUCAAGACUCCGACACCUGAACCAGCUGAGGUGGAGACUCGCAAGGUGGUGCUGAUGCAGUGCAACAUUGAGUCGGUGGAGGAGGGAGUCAAACACCACCUGACACUUCUGCUGAAGUUGGAGGACAAACUGAACCGGCACCUGAGCUGUGACCUGAUGCCAAAUGAGAAUAUCCCCGAGUUGGCGGCUGAGCUGGUGCAGCUGGGCUUCAUUAGUGAGGCUGACCAGAGCCGGUUGACUUCUCUGCUAGAAGAGACCUUGAACAAGUUCAAUUUUGCCAGGAACAGUACCCUCAACUCAGCCGCUGUCACCGUCUCCUCUUAGAGCUCACUCGGGCCAGGCCCUGAUCUGCGCUGUGGCUGUCCCUGGACGUGCUGCAGCCCUCCUGUCCCUUCCCCCCAGUCAGUAUUACCCUGUGAAGCCCCUUCCCUCCUUUAUUAUUCAGGAGGGCUGGGGGGGCUCCCUGGUUCUGAGCAUCAUCCUUUCCCCUCCCCUCUCUUCCUCCCCUCUGCACUUUGUUUACUUGUUUUGCACAGACGUGGGCCUGGGCCUUCUCAGCAGCCGCCUUCUAGUUGGGGGCUAGUCGCUGAUCUGCCGGCUCCCGCCCAGCCUGUGUGGAAAGGAGGCCCACGGGCACUAGGGGAGCCGAAUUCUACAAUCCCGCUGGGGCGGCCGGGGCGGGAGAGAAAGGUGGUGCUGCAGUGGUGGCCCUGGGGGGCCAUUCGAUUCGCCUCAGUUGCUGCUGUAAUAAAAGUCUACUUUUUGCUAAAA